GCGCGCACGUUGAGUGGCGGGGGAAGGCAGAAGAACUGCCCGAGGGAGGAGCGGCUCCGAGGACCGGGCAGCGCAUUUGGGGUGCCCGCUACAGGGCCCCCCAAGAGGCUGCCAGGUCGGGAGCGCAGCCUGAGGCCACGGGGGGAAGGGGGUGGGUGGGCUGAGAGCAGCUCGGCGGCGAGACUGGCCCGCCGCCCCUUCCCCCCACACCCGUCGACCUUGUGGGCAGAAGCUUCCCAGAGCUCCUUAGGCCGGCGCGAUGGCGACUGCUGUGGAGACGGAGGCCUGUCAGCCGACGGAUGCGAGUUGGGAAAGUGGCGGCGGCGGAGACGACGAGAUGAAGCAGGCGCUUCCGGAGCUUGAGUCCUCCCAACAAAAUGGCGGCGGCGGCGGCCUCAACAUCGCUGAGCCCAGCGGCGGCGCUGGGCGUGAGGAGAACGCGGGGGCCGAGGCCGCCCAGAGCCUCAGCCACGAGCAGCCUCAGGACUCCUCUGAGGCGGGCGCGGCCGCCCUGCCCAGAGGCCCCGAAGAGCCCGAAAGGCCUGUUAGGAGGAGUUUUCAGAUCCCCAGGAAGAGCAGAGAAAAGAAAGCACUUUUCCAGCCAUUAACUCCAGGCUCUCGAGAAUUUGAAGAUGUUGUAAAUAUUCUCCAUUCUUCUUACCUUGAACCAACCUCAGUAACAAAUUUUAACUACAGACGUGCUUGCUUGGUACACAAUGAGCUUUUGGAAAAGGAGUUUACAGAAAAGCGAAGAGAACUGAAGUUUGAUGGUCGUUUAGAUAAGGAACUUUCAGAAUCCUAUGCAUUUCUGAUGGUUGAUCGAUACCAGGUUCAAACCAUAUGUGAAAAAGGAUUACAUGUGGGUCAGUCCAAAAUAACAAUUCUUGGCAGUCCUUCCAUGGGUGUCUAUCUUUCUAGGUAUGCUGAUUUAUUACAAGCGAAUCCUUUGGACACGGGGGCAAUGGGUGAUGUUGUUAUUUUUAAAAUAAUGAAGGGUAAAAUAAAGAGUAUAUAUGACCCCAUGGGUGUAAAAAGUUUGGAAUCUAUGUUAAAUAAGAGUGCUUUGGACCCCACACCAAAGCAUGAAUGUCACGUGUCAAAGAAUGCCAAUCGAAUUACAUCACUUUUGGCUUACAGAGCCUAUGAGCUUACUCAGUAUUAUUUUUAUGAGUAUGGCUUUGAUGAGCUAAGGCGAAGACCAAGACACGUUUGUCCAUAUGCAGUUGUGUCUUUUACUUACAAAGAUGAUAUACAAACUCCGAAGUUUGUACCUUCAUCAAGAUCUAACAGCUUUAAUACAGAUAGAAACAUAGAUAAAUAUAACUAUACCUUGUGGAAAGGACAGCUUUUAAAUAAAGGAAAACUUUUGUGUUAUAUUUCUCUGAGGUCAGCCACUCGUGCUUUUUUGCCUAUCAAACUACCUGAGAAAUUAGAUGUUGAAACAGUUAUGAGUAUUGAUCAUCUGAAACAGAAAAUCCCUCCAGCACUGUUUUAUAAGGAAACAUACUUAGGUCCAAAUGAAGUUUUGAAGAAUGGAAUGUAUUGCAGCCUUUAUGAAGUUGUGGAAAAGACAAGAAUUGGAAGUAACAUGGAGAGUUUACUGCAAAAACUAGACAGAGAAAAACUUGUUCUUGUUAAACCUUUGGGAGACCGAGGAUACCUUUUUCUUCUCUCCCCUUAUCAGAUGGUUCCUCCAUAUGAAUAUCAGACUGCCAAGUCUCGAGUCCUACAUGCUUUGUUUCUAUUUCAAGAACCUAGAAGCAUAGUUACUUCACAAAAAGGUUCAACCAAUGCAGCACCACAGGAGAGGCAUGAGAGCAUGCCAGAUGUAUUAAAAAUAGCUCAGUUUUUACAAUUUUCUUUGAUUCAGUGUCGAAAGGAAUUCAAAAAUAUAAGCGCCAUAAAUUUUCAUUCUGUUGUUGAAAAGUAUGUAAGUGAAUUUUUUAAGCGAGGUUUUGGUUCAGGUAAACGAGAGUUUAUUAUGUUUCCAUAUGAUUCACGAUUAGAUGAUAAAAAAUUCUUAUACUCAGCUCCCAGAAAUAAAUCCCAUAUUGAUACUUGUUUGCAUGCCUAUAUUUUUCGGCCUGAAGUGUAUCAGUUACCUAUUUGUAAAUUAAAAGAACUAUUUGAAGAAAAUAGAAAACUUCAGCAGUUUAGUCCACUUUCAGAUUAUGAAGGUCAAGAAGAAGAAAUGAAUGGUACAAAAAUGAAAUUUGGAAAACGAAAUAACUCAAGAGGUGAAGCCAUUAUAUCUGGAAAGCAAAGAUCAUCUCAUUCUUUGGAUUAUGAUAAGGAUAGAGUCAAAGAAUUGAUUAAUUUAAUUCAGUGUAGGAAAAAGAGUGUGGGUGGGGACUCAGACACAGAAGAUAUGAGAAGCAAAACUGUCUUGAAGAGGAAGCUUGAGGAUCUACCUGAAAAUAUGAGAAAGCUCGCCAAAACCAGUAAUUUAUCUGAAAAUUGCCAUCUGUAUGAAGAGUCUCCACAGCCUAUUGGCUCACUUGGACAUGAUGCUGACUUGAGGCGGCAGCAGCAGGAUACCUGUAACUCCGGCAUUGCUGACAUCCAUAGGCUGUUUAAUUGGUUAUCAGAAACACUAGCAAAUGCGCGCCAUUCUGAUGCAUCUCUGACAGACACAGUCAACAAAGCCUUAGGAUUGAGCACUGAUGAUGCCUAUGAAGAGCUGAGGCAAAAACAUGAGUAUGAGUUGAACUCUACCCCAGAUAAGAAAGACUAUGAGCAGCCUACUUGUGCAAAAGUUGAAAAUGCACAGUUUAAGGGUACUCAGAGCUUAUUACUAGAAGUUGAUGCAACAUCUAAGUAUUCUGUUGCUAUUUCUACCAGCGAAGUGGGCACUGACCAUAAGCUACAUUUGAAAGAAGAUCCAAAUUUAAUUAGCGUGAAUAAUUUUGAAGAUUGCAGUUUGUGUCCCAGUGUUCCCAUUGAACAUGGAUUUCGUAGACAACAGUCUAAGUCAAAUAAUGUUGAAGAGACUGAAAUACAUUGGAAACUGAUUCCAAUUACAGGAGGGAAUGCAAGAAGCCCAGAAGACCAGCUGGGGAAACAUGGUGAGAAACAAACACCAGGUAUGAAAUCACCAGAAGAACAACUGGUGUGUGUGCCACCACAGGAGGCCUUUCCUAACGACCCCCGGGUAAUAAAUAGACAGAGAAGUUCUGAUUACCAGUUUCCAUCCUCUCCAUUUACAGACACACUAAAGGGCACCACUGAGGAUGACGUGUUGACAGGUCAGGUGGAGGAGCAGUGUGUGCCAGCAGCAGAGGCAGAGCCGCCUGCAGUGAGCGAAACCACAGAGAGGACAGUGUUAGGAGAGUACAAUCUCUUUUCUAGGAAGAUAGAAGAGAUUUUGAAGCAAAAGAAUGUUUCAUAUGUCAGUACAGUUUCCACACCUAUCUUUUCAACACAAGAGAAGAUGAAACGGCUUUCCGAGUUCAUAUAUUCUAAGACUUCCAAAGCUGGUGUGCAGGAGUUUGUAGAUGGUUUGCAUGAGAAGCUAAAUACUAUUAUUAUUAAAGCAUCAGCCAAGGGUGGGAAUUUGCCACCAGUCAGUCCUAACGAUUCUGGUGCUAAGAUAGCAUCGAAUCCUCUGGAAAGGCAUGUCAUACCAGUUUCCUCAAGUGACUUCAACAAUAAACAUCUCCUUGAGCCACUGUGUAGUGAUCCUUUGAAAGAUACCAACUCUGAUGAGCAGCAUUCCACUUCGGCUUUAACUGAAGUAGAAAUGAACCAGCCUCAACAUGCCACAGAGUUAAUGGUGACUUCUGAUCAUAUUGUACCUGGUGAUAUGGCCCGGGAACCAGUAGAAGAAACAACAAAAUCCCCCAGUGAUGUAAACAUUUCUGCUCAACCAGCUCUUUCAAAUUUUAUAAGCCAGUUAGAACCUGAAGUAUUUAAUAGUUUGGUUAAAAUCAUGAAAGACGUCCAGAAAAAUACUGUGAAAUUUUAUAUUCAUGAAGAAGAAGAGAGUGUGCUCUGUAAAGAAAUAAAGGAAUAUCUUAUCAAAUUAGGCAAUACAGAAUGUCAUCCUGAACAGUUUUUGGAAAGAAGAUCAAAAUUAGAUAAACUAUUGAUUAUUAUUCAAAAUGAAGACAUUGCAGGUUUCAUUCACAAGAUACCUGGCUUGGUGACUUUAAAGAAGCUCCCCUGUGUUAGUUUUGCUGGUGUUGAUAGCCUGGAUGAUGUUAAAAAUCAUACAUACAAUGAAUUAUUUGUAUCUGGAGGUUUUAUCGUAUCUGAUGAAUCAAUUCUAAACCCAGAGGUUGUCACAGUUGAGAACCUUAAAAAUUUUUUGACAUUCCUUGAGGAACUUAGUACUCCAGAAGGAAAAUGGCAAUGGAAAGUCCACUGUAAAUUUCAGAAGAAACUAAAGGAACUAGGCAGAUUGAAUGCUAAAGCUCUAAGUCUGUUGACGCUUCUGAAUGUCUAUCAGAAGAAACAUCUGGUUGAAAUUUUGUCAUACCACAAUUGUGAUUCACAAACUCGAAAUGCUCCAGAAUUGGAUUGCCUUAUCAGACUUCAGGCUCAGAACAUACAGCAACGACACAUAGUCUUUUUAACAGAGAAGAACAUCAAGAUGCUUUCCAGUUAUACAGAUAAUGGAAUAGUGGUUGCAACUGCUGAAGACUUCAUGCAAAACUUUAAAAAUCUUGUGGGCUAUCACAAUUCAAUCACAGAAGAAAACCUUCCACAGCUUGGUGCUAAUGAGAAUCUUGAGUCGCAGUCAGAUGCUGUUUUGACAUUAACCCCUUUGGAGCUGGGAGUUGGGAUUUCCCAACAUUAAACGUGAACACAUUUCGCAGAAGCUUUUAGCAUCGGAUUAUCUGGACAUUCACAUCUAGUGUGAGUGUUGUGACUAAGUGAACUUGUGGCAGAAGACCAAGCUUUAAGGGAUUGUGGACUUGCAGACCCUGACGCGUUAUAUUGUGUGAGUAGUGUAUAAUUUUAAAACUUAAACAAACUGUGUAUUUCAAUAGAGGAGGACUUUUUGUUUUUUAAAUGUAGCUCUUUUAGAAAACGAUGAAAAGGAUGAAGAGGAUAUGUCUCUGGAUUCAGGGGAUGAAAUCUCACAUAUAGAAGUAUGCAGCAAUUUUCAUUCAGAAAUAUGGGAGAAAGAGACCAAAGGAUCACGUGGAACAGAUCAAAAAAAGAAUACUCAAAUUGAGUUGCAAUCGUCUCCUGAUGUGCAAAACAGUUUAUUAGAAGAUAAGACUUACCUUGAUUCUGAAGAGAGAACUUCUAUUGAUAUAGUAUGCUCUGAAGGAGAGAACAGCAAUUCAACAGAACAAGAUUCAUAUAGUAACUUUCAGGUUUAUCAUAGUCAAUUAAAUAUGUCCCAUCAGUUUAGUCAUUUUAAUGUUCUCACUCAUCAGACAUUUUUGGGGACACCAUAUGCCCUUUCAUCAAGUCAGUCUCAAGAAAAUGAGAAUUACUUCUUAUCUGCUUAUACUGAAAGCUUGGAUAGAGAUAAAUCUCCACCUCCCUUAAGUUGGGGGAAAAGUGAUUCUUCCAGGCCAUAUUCACAAGAGAAAUAACUGUAGUAACUUUUUUUUUAAGAGAUUGUUGUGGACUUUGUUUAUUAACAAUUUAUAUUUCAUUCUCUAAACAAAAGGUUCUUGUUCUUUCUCAAAUGUUUUUUCUUUUAUUUAAAUCAUGAUGGCCUGUAACAGUUGAAGCAUCUAAAAAUUGAAAUAAAUAUAUAUUUUUAACAUAUAUUGUACUUGAAUUAUCUCAUGUUGGCACUUCUAAGUUUUACUUUUUGUAUGUUACCUGUACUUAGGCUUCAAAUUGAAGCCUGUUUUAUGUGUAAAAUCAGAUGCUUGCAGGAGGACGGUAAACAGCAAAGGCUUUACUUCUUUUUCUCUAAUGUCACCUGAUAUAAAGUACUUUUGUUGAAGUGAAUUAUUUUGAUGUAGGCUUUUGUAUACUGUGUUUACACAGGUAUAAGUCAGUAAUAGCAGUGUUAAUAUUUACAGGAUUUUGGCUCGAUACCUCAAGAUUUAUCUAACAGUGCAGUUUCAUUUAGAUAAUAAACUAUGUACAUAGGACACAUUUUUUAUCUCUAGGCUUAGUCAUGUAAAAACUGCCUAUUGCUAAAAUUCUGGUAACUUUUUGAGAGUAUUGGAUAAUUUUCAGUACCUGCGCAAUCCUUGAUUUAAUGAAAUUAAAUUUUUUAUUUCAAAAGAUAGGCUUCUGUUUAUCAAAGGCGUUGAACAAUUUGAUUUUUAAAUUAGUUUUAGCAAAAUGGAAGUAUAAUGGGAAUAUAUUUUUGAGGUGGUCUUAGUAGUAAUUACCAUUUGUUGAACACAUUAAUGCUAUACUAGACAGAUACAGUGGAGAUAGCUUUCAAACCCGUAUCUAUUCCUAACUACUGCCUCUAAUACUAAUUACUAACUUGUUACUAAUGCUAACUUUUAAAAAUGUUUUUGAAAAUUGCAAUUUCUACAAAUAAAUGUCAUAGUGCAAAUAAAUGUCAGGAUUUAGAGAAGGAGCCUAAACUGAAUUUGUGUUAUUUCAGUAAAAGUUAUGGAGUUAUGGGUCUAGACGUGUUAAUAAGUUAGACAGAACUUUGGCACUUUAGAACAAAUGCAUGAGUGGUAUUUCAGUUCCUAAGUUACAUAAAAAGUGUGAAAGAACACUGUGAGGUCCCAGCAACGCCAGACUAUAUUAAGGUAAGUAGAAAGUGUUUUUAUAGGGCUUCAAUACCCAGGUGGUGACAGAGCAGAAGAACCGGUUUUUUUUUUUUUUUUUUUACUACUAAGCUUUUACAAAAGAAGUAUCUGUUUUAUUGUAUAGAACAAGUACAGCAUUUUACUACAUAGUAUACAAGUUUUUAAUGAGCAUUUAAAAAAAUAAGUAAAUCUAGGCUAUUUGAAAAAUACAGUUGAGCCAGUGAGCACAUUUUAUAAUUUGGAAGACACAAAUCAAAUGUGAAGGAUUUGAUUUUCUACAUUUAAAAUGAAGAACCAAAACUCUCUUCUUGAUUUUCAGCUAAAGGCAGGAGACUACUUUCCAACUCCUUUUGCUUCUGGAGAAGGCCCUGAAAUCACAUUGAUAUAUGUUUGUUAGUAAAAUGUGCACACCUGACUUGCAAUGUUGUGUUAAACUAGAAUUAUAUUCACUUGGAAAACAUAUCGCUUAGGAUAAAAUUUUGUCAUUCAAAAAUUUUUUCAGAAAUGCUUGUACUAGACCACCUCAUUUGGAUAUAUAGCUAUCACAUUUGUAAGAUUCUGUUUUUAGCAUAAAAAUCAAUAGGGAUGAAAAUUUUCUUAGAACUCAAGACUCCAUAACUAUGGGGGUAAAUGAAGUCAUCCCUUCUCCCCCAGUCCACCCCCAAGUGCUCUUAGAUACUGAAGGAGUCUCCCUUAACAUACAGUGUUUUUUUUUUGUUGUUGUUGUUUUGUUUUUUUUUGGAGAUGGAGUCUCGCUCUGUCGCCCAAGCUGGAGUACAGUGGUGCAAUCUCACUGCAAGCUCUGCCUCCCAGGUUCACACCAUUCUCCUGCCUCAACCUCCCGAAUGGCUGGGACUACAGGCACCCACCACCACGCCUGGCUAACUAACUAACUAACUUUUUGUAUUUUUAGUAGAGACAGGGUUUCACUGUGUUAGCCAGGAUGGUCUUGAUCUCCUGACCUCAUGAUCUGCCUGCCUCAGCCUCCCAAAGUGCUGGGAUUACAGGCUUGAGCCACUGCUCCUGGCCAACAUCCAGUAUUUUAUCUUGACUGUCCUAACCUUACCUUAGAUGCUAACAGAAGGGUCCUGCUGAAAUAACACUGGGUGCUAUAUUGAUGGGUAAAUGUGUACAUCCUAUUCCUUCCUCUUUAUCUCACAAUUUUUGUCUCCACUAAGCAAGAAGUAAACUAACACUUCGUCACUCUAAAGAAAUAACUUAUGUAAAACUCUUAGUAACCCUGUUUGUCUUCAAAUGAGUAAAUAGACCAAAGUGGGGGGACAAUUUUCUAGUUCUGUAGAGGGAAAAACAUCUGAGUCAACAUUUUGAAAUGCAGAGGGUAUUGGUACAUGACGACAUGGAAAAGGGCACUUUUAAACACAGCUUACUCUUCCUCAAGUACAGAGAGUAUAUAGUGAAUCAAAACUAACUACAGCCAUUCUUUUUAAAGCCCAAGGGAUGGAGCAAAGGUGUAAGGAUGUUACCUGUUUGUUUUAAUCAGAGAGCAAAAAGAAGUCACAAUAGUUUGGGAGAAAAAGUAGUAUGGUGAGUAAGGUUAUGCGUAUAAUUUCAUACUGAAUUUAUUACUAUUUGGGAUGUACGUCAAUGUUCUAACAAACACUGCCAACACGUCAAUUUUUUAAAAAGCGUGGGCCACAUUGCUAAGAAUUUGUUAAAGCAUAACUGUAUUUUUUGUUUUAGGGCCUUAUUGAUGUUUUGCCGUUCCAAUGUAUGCAUUUUUUUACUCAAUAAACUUGUCUUAAUUUUA